GCGGGCCUGGAGCCGGGAUCCGCCCUAGGGGCUCGGAUCGCCGCGCGCUCGCCGCUCGCCCGCCAGCCCGCCCGUGGUCCGUGGCGGCGCGCUCCACCCGGCACGGGGAGGCGCGGGGCGCACCAUGGCCGCAGACACGCCGGGGAAACCGAGCGCCUCGCCGAUGGCAGGAGCGCCGGCCAGCGCCAGCCGGACCCCAGACAAGCCCCGGAGCGCGGCCGAGCACCGCAAGGUGGGGUCCCGGCCGGGCGUGAGGGGGGCGACCGGGGGGCGGGAGGGACGCGGGACUCAGCCGGUGCCCGACCCGCAGUCCUCCAAGCCGGUCAUGGAGAAGCGGCGCCGAGCGCGUAUUAACGAGAGCCUCGCUCAGCUCAAAACCCUCAUCCUGGACGCCCUCAGAAAAGAGAGCUCCCGCCACUCGAAGCUGGAGAAGGCGGACAUCCUGGAGAUGACCGUGAGACACCUGCGGAGCCUGCGUCGCGUGCAGGUGACGGCCGCGCUCAGCGCCGACCCCGCCGUUCUGGGCAAGUACCGCGCCGGCUUCCACGAGUGUCUGGCGGAGGUGAACCGCUUCCUGGCCGGCUGCGAGGGCGUCCCGGCCGACGUGCGCUCCCGCCUGCUGGGCCACCUGGCAGCCUGCCUGCGCCAGCUGGGACCCUCCCGCCGCCCGGCCUCGCUGUCCCCGGCUGCCCCCGCAGAGGCCCCAGCGCCCGAGGUCUACGCGGGCCGCCCGCUGCUGCCAUCGCUCGGCGGCCCCUUCCCUCUGCUCGCGCCGCCGCUGCUGCCGGGUCUGACCCGGGCGCUGCCCGCCGCCCCCAGGGCGGGGCCGCAGGGCCCGGGUGGGCCCUGGAGGCCGUGGCUGCGCUGAGGCUGUGGCCCUGAGACUGCAUCGGAGGCGGCGCCCCGUUCUAGGGCCGUGGCCUUUGCCGAGACUGUAGCAGAGAAAACGUAUUUAUUAUUCCA